GGCCCUUCCACCUUUUGUGGGCACUCAAGUUCGGACCUCUGGGAUCGGCGAUUCCCCUCUGGCCAGGGCUGGUUUUAAUGCUCUCCGUGGGCGGGCUUCGGUUGAGUUUGGUCCGCUUUUCCUUUCUGCUCCUCAGGGGAGCAUUGCUUCCUUCUCUCGCAGUGACCAUGACGAAAUUAGCGCAGUGGCUUUGGGGACUAGCGAUCCUGGGCUCCACCUGGGUGGCCCUGACCACGGGAGCCUUGGGCCUGGAGCUGCCCUUGUCCUGCCAGGAAGUCCUGUGGCCACUGCCCGCCUACUUGCUGGUGUCCGCCGGCUGCUAUGCCCUGGGCACUGUGGGCUAUCGUGUGGCCACUUUUCAUGACUGCGAGGACGCCGCACGCGAGCUGCAGAGCCAGAUACAGGAGGCCCGAGCCGACUUAGCCCGCAGGGGGCUGCGCUUCUGACAGCCUAACCCCAUUCCUGUGCGGACAGCCCUUCCUCCCAUUUCCCAUUAAAGAGCCAGUUUAUUUUCUAA